AGGCUGGGCCGGUGGGAGAGGGAGGCGAGCCGACCGCUGGGCUGCUGGGCUCCCGCGCCCUCGCGCUCCCCGCCGCCAGCCCAGGCGCAGGCAGGGCGCAGGCGGCGGCGGGCGGCAUGGAGAGCCUGCUGGAGAAUCCGGUGCGCGCCGUGCUCUACCUCAAGGAGCUCACGGCCAUCGUGCAGAACCAGCAGAGCCUCAUCCACACCCAGCGAGAGCGUAUCGACGAGCUGGAGCGGCGGCUGGACGAGCUGAGCGCUGAGAACCGCAGCCUGUGGGAGCACCAGCAGCUGCUGCAAGCCCAGCCUCCGCCCGGGCUCGUCCCCCCGUCAUCGGCCCCGCUGCCGGCCGCUCCGGCCACCGCUCCUGCCGCCGCCGCCAGGGCCCAGGAACCUCUCCAGGACCAGGGACAGCGCUCAGCAGCCGCGCCGCAUCCCGCGCCCGAUCGGCCGCCGCGUCAGCACCACGGACAGCUCCUGGAGCAGCCCCAGCGGGGCCCUGGCAGCAGGGCUCACACACCCCAGUCGCCCCACAAGCAUCUGGGGACACAAGGGGCCGUGACUGACAAGGAGAAGGAGCGUCCCCCGAGUUGCUGCGCUGCUGCCGGAGCCCUCCUUCAGCACAAAUCCCCCUCCGCCCUCGGCAAGGGCGUCCUGAGCAGGAGACCUGAGAAUGAGACCGUGCUGCACCAGUUCUGCUGCCCAGCCGCCGACGCCUGCUCCGACCUGGCCUCCCAAAGUGAUGGCUCCUGCACCCAGGCCGGUGGGGGCAUGGAGGACUCCGUGGUGGCAGCGGCGGCGGUGGCAGCCGGCAGACCCAGUGCCCAUGCCCCGAAGGCUCAAGCCCAGGAGCUGCAGGAGGAGGAGGAGCGGCCGGGGGCAGGGGCUGCCUCCCCAAGGGCUGGCCCCCAGCACAAGGCCUCCCCCGGCCGGCAGCAGCCUGCCCUGGCGACGGCGCUGUGCCCCCACGCCCCUGCCGCCUCCGAUUACGAACUCUCCCUUGACCUAAAGAAUAAACAGAUUGAAAUGCUAGAACAUAAGUACGGCGGUCACCUGGUGUCCCGGCGCGCCGCUUGCACCAUCCAAACCGCCUUCCGCCAAUACCAGCUCAGCAAGAACUUCGAGAAAAUCCGCAACUCGCUUCUGGAGAGCCGCCUGCCACGGCGGAUCUCCCUGCGCAAGGUGCGGUCACCCACGGCCGAGAGCCUGGCGGCCGAGAAAGCGCUCAUGGAGGGCUACGGCCUCGUGGGGCUGCCGCUGGUGCGCUCGCCCUCCCUGCCGCCCACCUUCGCAGGCACCCUCACCGAGCUGGAGGACUCCUUCACCGAGCAGGUGCAAUCCCUGGCCAAGUCCAUCGACGACGCGCUCAGCACGUGGAGCCUCAAGACCAUGUGCUCCCUGCGGGAGAGUGGCGCUUACCAGCUCCACCAGGCCCUGCAGGCGGCCGCGGGGCCCCCAGGCCUGGAGGCCGAGGGGCGGGCGCCGGAGAGCGCGGGCCCCGGGCCCGGGGAUGACGCCGCGGAGACCCCCGGCCUGCCCCCGGCCCACAGCGGGACCCUCAUGAUGGCUUUCCGGGACGUCACGGUGCAGAUCGCCAACCAGAACAUAUCCGUCUCCUCCUCCACGGCUCUGUCGGUGGCCAACUGCCUGGGCGCUCAGACGGUCCAGGCCCCCGCAGAGCCCGCGGCGGGCAAGGCCGAGCAGGGCGAGACCUCUGGGCGGGAGGCCCCGGAAGCCCCCGCCGUGGGCCGGGAGGACGCGUCAGCCGAGGACUCAUGCGCAGAGGCUGCGGCUAGUGGGGCGGCGGAUGGGGCCACAGCCCCCAAAACAGAGGAGGAAGAGGAGGAGGAGGAGACGGCGGAGGUGGGGAGAGGGGCCGAGGCCGAGGCAGGCGACUUGGAGCAGCUGAGCAGCAGCAGCACGUCCACCAAGUCCGCCAAGUCAGGCUCGGAGGCGUCGGCCUCCGCCUCCAAGGACGCCCUGCAGGCCAUGAUCCUGAGCCUGCCGCGCUACCACUGCGAGAACCCAGCCAGCUGCAAGUCGCCCACGCUCUCCACCGACACCCUGCGCAAGCGGCUCUACCGCAUCGGCCUCAACCUCUUCAACAUAAACCCCGACAAGGGCAUCCAGUUCCUGAUCUCACGCGGCUUCAUCCCGGACACCCCCAUCGGUGUGGCCCAUUUCCUCCUCCAGCGAAAGGGCCUCAGCCGCCAGAUGAUUGGAGAGUUCCUGGGCAACAGCAAGAAGCAGUUCAACCGCGACGUGCUGGACUGCGUGGUGGACGAGAUGGACUUCUCCAGCAUGGAGCUGGACGAGGCCCUGCGCAAGUUCCAGGCACACAUCCGUGUGCAGGGGGAGGCUCAGAAGGUGGAGCGGCUCAUUGAGGCCUUCAGCCAGCGCUACUGCAUGUGCAACCCCGAAGUGGUUCAGCAGUUCCACAACCCCGACACCAUCUUCAUCCUCGCCUUCGCCAUCAUCCUCCUCAACACCGACAUGUACAGCCCCAACAUCAAGCCUGACCGGAAGAUGAUGCUGGAGGACUUCAUCCGAAACCUUCGAGGUGUGGACGAUGGCGCUGACAUCCCCAGGGAGCUGGUGGUAGGCAUCUAUGAGAGGAUACAGCAGAAGGAGCUCAAGUCCAAUGAGGACCACGUCACGUACGUCACCAAGGUGGAGAAGUCCAUUGUGGGCAUGAAGACAGUGCUGUCCGUGCCCCACCGCCGCCUGGUGUGCUGCAGCCGGCUCUUCGAGGUGACGGAUGUGAACAAGCUGCAGAAGCAGGCAGCGCAUCAGAGGGAGGUGUUCCUCUUCAAUGACCUGCUGGUGAUUCUCAAACUUUGCCCGAAGAAGAAGAGCUCCUCCACGUACACCUUUUGCAAGUCAGUUGGCCUGCUGGGCAUGCAGUUCCAGCUCUUUGAGAACGAGUAUUACUCUCAUGGCAUCACACUGGUGACCCCGCUCUCGGGCUCCGAGAAGAAGCAGGUGCUGCAUUUCUGUGCCCUGGGCUCGGACGAGAUGCAGAAGUUCGUGGAGGACCUGAAGGAGUCCAUUGCUGAGGUGACGGAGCUGGAGCAGAUCCGAAUAGAGUGGGAGCUGGAGAAGCAGCAGGGAACAAAGACACUCUCCUUCAAGCCCUGCGGAGCCCAGGGGGACCCACAGUCAAAGCAAGGAUCGCCGACAGCCAAAAGGGAAGCCGCGCUCAGGGAGAGGCCGGCGGAGAGCACGGUGGAGGU